GAGUGCGCAGGACUGGCAAGAGGGAAGCCGGGCUGCUCCACGCCUUUCACGCCUUCCACCUCCUGCGUGUCCAUCUGUGAGAAGGAGCCAGAGCCCAAGGGAGAUGAUGGAGCCUGAGGAGUACAGAGAGAGAGGGAGAGAGAUGGUGGAUUACAUCUGCCAGUACCUGAGCACUGUGCGGGAGAGACGUGUGACGCCAGACGUGCAGCCUGGCUACCUGCGAGCCCAGCUGCCUGAGAGUGCUCCUGAGGACCCCGACAGCUGGGACAGCAUCUUUGGGGACAUUGAACGAAUCAUCAUGCCUGGGGUGGUACAUUGGCAGAGCCCCCAUAUGCACGCCUACUACCCAGCCCUCACCUCUUGGCCCUCCCUGCUAGGAGACAUGCUGGCUGAUGCCAUCAACUGCUUGGGAUUCACCUGGGCAUCCAGCCCUGCGUGUACAGAGCUGGAGAUGAACGUCAUGGACUGGUUGGCAAAAAUGCUGGGACUUCCAGAGCACUUCUUGCACCACCACCCCAGCAGCCAGGGCGGAGGCGUCCUGCAGAGCACGGUCAGUGAAUCCACUUUGAUUGCCCUGCUGGCAGCAAGGAAGAACAAAAUCCUGGAAAUGAAAACGUCUGAGCCCGAUGCUGAUGAGUCCUGCCUAAAUGCCCGACUCGUGGCCUAUGCCUCUGACCAGGCUCACUCCUCUGUGGAAAAGGCUGGUUUGAUUUCCCUUGUGAAGAUGAAAUUUCUGCCUGUGGAUGACAACUUCUCACUCCGAGGGGAAGCUCUUCAGAAGGCCAUCGAGGAAGACAAGCAGCGGGGCUUGGUGCCCGUCUUUGUCUGUGCAACACUAGGGACCACUGGGGUCUGUGCAUUUGACUGCCUGUCAGAGCUGGGCCCCAUCUCCAAAGCACAUCAUCCUUGCAGCCCACCACUCAGCUUGGCCAGGUGCGAGACAUCUUUCCCCACUUCAUACCUCCCCUCCGGCCAGGUGAUGUUUGCCUCCUCAGGUGCCCGUGAGGGGCUGUGGCUCCACAUCGAUGCUGCUUAUGCAGGCACUGCCUUCCUGUGCCCCGAGUUCCGGGGGUUUCUGAAGGGGAUUGAGUAUGCCGACUCCUUCACCUUUAAUCCUUCCAAGUGGAUGAUGGUGCAUUUUGACUGUACUGGGUUCUGGGUCAAGGACAAGUACAAGCUGCAGCAGACCUUCAGUGUGAAUCCCAUCUACCUCAGGCAUGCCAACUCAGGCGUGGCCACCGACUUCAUGCACUGGCAGAUCCCCCUGAGCCGACGGUUUCGCUCUGUUAAACUCUGGUUCGUGAUUCGGUCCUUCGGGGUGAAGAAUCUUCAAGCACAUGUCAGACAUGGUACUGAAAUGGCUAAAUAUUUUGAAUCUCUGGUCAGAAACGACCCUUCCUUUGAAAUUCCUGCCAAGAGGCACCUUGGCCUGGUGGUUUUUCGUCUAAAGGGUCCUAAUUGUCUCACAGAAAAUGUGUUAAAGGAAAUAGCUAAAGCUGGCCGUCUCUUCCUCAUCCCGGCCACUAUCCAGGACAAGUUAAUCAUCCGUUUCACUGUGACAUCCCAGUUUACCACUAGGGAUGACAUCCUGAGAGACUGGAAUCUCAUUCGAGAUGCUGCCACUCUCAUCCUGAGUCAGCACUGUACUUCCCAACCCAGCCCUCGGGUUGGGAACCUCAUCUCCCAAAUCAGGGGUGCCAGAGCCUGGGCCUGUGGAACGUCCCUUCAGUCUGUCAGUGGGGCAGGAGAUGAUCCAGUCCAGGCCAGGAAGAUCAUCAAGCAGCCUCAGCGUGUGGGAGCCGGUCCCAUGAAAAGGGAAAAUGGCCUCCAUCUUGAAACCCUGCUGGACCCAGUUGAUGACUGCUUUUCAGAAGAGGCCCCAGAUGCCACCAAGCACAAGCUGUCCUCCUUCCUGUUCAGUUACUUGUCUGUGCAGACUAAGAAGAAGACGGUGCGCUCCCUCAGUUGCAACAGUGUGCCAGUGAGUGCUCAGAAGCCACUGCCCACAGAGGCCUCUGUGAAGAAUGGGGGCUCCUCCAGGGUCAGAAUCUUUUCCAGGUUUCCAGAAGACAUGAUGAUGCUGAAGAAAAGUGCCUUCAAAAAACUCAUCAAAUUCUACAGCGUCCCCAGCUUUCCUGAAUGCAGCUCUCAAUGUGGACUCCAGCUGCCCUGUUGCCCUCUGCAGGCCAUGGUUUAGACACAGGGCCUUCAGCCAGAGUCUGAGGAUAUACUUCAGGGACUCUGUGAACCCCUCACAAUUGUAUGCCAACUUUGUGUGCUUAUGUGUACAUGCAUUUUUCUUGGGGCGAGUUCAUAAUUUUAAUCAAAUUCUCAUAGGGGUUCAUGACCCACAAUAGGAUACAAACGAAGAGUUUAAGCCAGCAUGAUCCAGAUGGGUUCAGCAGUCUGGUCAGUGAGAAAGGGCCGAGGGUAGACAGGCAGCUUCUGUGGUUCAGCUUGUGACAUGAUAUAUAACACAGAAAUAAAUUAUGCUUGUCCCUGAAACAAAA